AUUGUUUGGAGCCAGGUAGAGUGAAGUCCUACAGAGUUAUCAGGUUCCAGACCCUGCCUUCUCUUCUGAAAGGUAAGUUCUGCUAUAUAUAUAUAUACAUAUAUAUAAAUAUAUUUUUUUAAUAGUAUAUUAUUGUGAUACUUUACAGAAGAGUGACUUGCAUGGGAUCAAGAAACUUAAUAGAAAAGAGCAAUGUGGUGCUCCUUCGAGCUGUUUGUUAUUCCUACUUACUUGAGUGCAUUUAGUCUUGUUCAAAGGGCUGUCCCUGUUUCCUUCUCAAAUGUCCUUUGUAGUUUGCAGAUGCUGGCAGGUUUGCCUAACUUUUUCAUGUUCUUUUCCUGCUAACUCCUCACUGCAGUUUUUCAGGUUUUCCUGCUCUGAACACUGAAUUCUUUUACGUCCCGUAUCUAUGUUGGCUCUGUUUCAGCUCCAGGGAUUUACACACAGUUUCCAAAUAGUUUUUCUAUAAUAGUUCCACAGUAAAAUAACGUCUUGUGAAAUAAGAAGAUCCUACCUCAUUCUGUUCUUCUAAUUAAGGCUGAGUCUCAAAAGAGGAUUCCAGUAAGUGUUAAAUACAGCAAAUCAGAAGUUUUUUUUUUUUUUUUCUUUUUUUUUUUUUGUUAUGUUACUAGAUCUGAGCAUGCUGUGACUGGCAGGAUCUGGAUAGAAAAUCAGAUGUUGGCUAAACGAAGAGGCCUUAUAUCACUAGGAUUAAAUUAGAGAUAAUGGUGUGAUUUUAUAAGCGCAUACUAGGAAAUAUGUCUUAAGGAGGGCCUGUUUGGAUGAUUGUGAAAAAUGAGGUGUAGCUGAUGUUUGCUGCAUUGAAAGAAGGUGAAGUGGGGAUUUUCUGCCCCUUCUCCAAGUACCAUGUGCAGAGCUUCUCUUUUGGUUCCAUUCUUUGUUUUUUUGCUGGCAUCUAGUAGCACCUGACUCCUUUAGAGAUGGCCUACGCAGGGAGUGAUGGCGAAGCUGGAUUUCUUGUGGGUGGAGCUAAGCAUAGGAAGACCAACGUUCGAUUUUCAAUUUUCACUUUGUGCAGUAUGAGUUCCUAGCUUUUAUUACAAAACCAAAUGCUUCCAGUGUUCUCCUGUUACUUUUGGAGUUUCCAUAUUUUAAUUGUUUGAACUAUACAUGCUUUCCAAAUAAAUGGGAAGUAUGAGUCUCACAUUCUAAGGGAAGAAUGUGUCUUAGGGAAAAGCCCUCCCAGGCGAAUUCAGAUCCCUCUAUGUCCUUCUGAAAACACAGUAUGUAUUUGCAACCCAGCAGUCAGUCACUGGCAGAAUUUUGCAACGAUUUCCCAGUUUCGUUGGCACGACUCCAGGACAAGGUUCUUUGUAAUUCUUUGCUCAAACAUAAGGAGGAUCACAUAUAAAUAAAACUCUUAGCAGACAGAUCAGUGAAUUAUAAUCAUCUUUCAGUUUUAAAAGCUACAACAUAAUAAGGCGCUCUCUUUUUUUUUUUUGAGAGAGGCGGCGAAACAGUAACAAAUCAUGAUGCUAUAAUGUGAACAAAGUGGUAGCUUUGGAGGGCACAGGGGGAAAACAAGCACAACCGUUUUUGCUCAGAAAAUAAUUCAGUAGCAACAAGGUCUGAGAGCCAGGAAUCUCCUUGUUCUUACUGAAACGAUUAUUUGUCAAAAUAUUUGAUUGUUUCCCUAUUCCCCCUGAAAAGUUUGGACUUUUCUUUUUGCUCGAUUUUGACACUAGAAUUUUUAACUAUCAGUGCUAUUGUGUUUACAGCAUUCAAGGUCUCGGAGUUCAAAGGUUAUCCAUUAACAUGUAGAAUGAGGUUACACUUCAGGCUCAACCUGGUUCCACUUGGUCAUAGUUUCUUUGUUGUGUAGCAAGGCUCAUAGUCAUUUGUUUUCAUAAAGUUAAAUGAAGUUUCUUGUUUAUGAAGUGUUUUUGGACUGUGUUUUAGAAUGUGACAAUAAGUUUAAAAAAUAUAUUUUAAAGAUAGGUAUUCAUCCUUUGUCAGAAAAGGAAUCCUAAUACUAAAAGUGAUCAAUAUCAGUGGACUUGAGUGAAAAAAAAUUCACCCAAUUUAGUUUUUUAGUGCUGGCCUAAGAAUCUACUGGCACUGCUAAUUAAUUGUGAGUAAUUGAUUCGCUUCCUUUUUAAAAAAGACUAACCAGACCAUAUGUGGGGUUAGUAGUUAUAUAUAAAAUGACAGCAAAACAUGACACUUGGCAAAUUCUUCCCCUUUGCUGAGCUGUCUUCUCAAAUUCCUUUUCCUAUUUAUUAAGAUUGCAUUGCUCACCAGCUCCGGAUCGUUUCUGUAGUGCGUUCUUUCUUUUGAUUUAGGAAAUAGAUAUUUUAAAUGCUUUUCUUGAUGUGUUUUAAAGUUUUUUCAUUUUGGAUAUGCUGAAGGCCGGUAAAAACACAAAUAUUUGGCUAUUUUGUUAGUAGCGACUUGCAUAGAUCCAUUUCACAUUUGCAUUAGUUUGCAUUUUGGGGUAGAAAAAUUGUGGAUGUGCUUGUUAUGUCUAUGGUUCCUCGAAGCUUAUUUAAAAUGGGGAAAUAUCACAGGCCUUAGGAAUCAGGAUCUUUUUUUUGUCCUUUUUUUCAGUAAGGAAAGAAAACAUUUGGGAAACGCUUUAAAUGAGUUGUGCGUAGGGAGGAGGGGAAAGGGUAGCGGUUUUUUUUUUUUUUUUUUUGUCCCUUUUUUUGUCCCCGGUUUCCUCCAAAUGGAUUUCUAUCAAAACCAAGUAGAUUCUUGGAACCUAGGCUAAGUUUAGAAAUCUCAAGUUAGAAUAGCGCAAGCCCAGCCCUUUCAGAAAAAAAAAAAUCACAACAAUUAAAUAGCUUUCUGAAGAUACUCAUUUAAAAACUGUUUAUCUUCUCGACCUUCCUCAAGCUUGAAGAAAAUCUUUGGUGUUUUUCGCGCACAGCUGCCUUCUAACCCGCGAGCAACGGCGUUAAGGGUUUGGAAAUCCCUUGUCUCCAGGUUGCUGGGAUUGACUUCUUGCUCAAUUGAAACACUCAUUCAAUGGAGACAAAGAGAACUAAUGCUUUGUGCUGAUUCAUAUUUGAAUCGAGGCAUUGGGAACCCUGUAUGCCUUGUUUGUGGAAAGAACCAGUGACACCAUCACUGAGCUUCCUAAAAGUUCGAAGAAGUUAGAGGACUAUACACUUUCUUUUGAACUUUUAUAAUAAAUAUUUGCUCUGGUUUUUGGAACCCAGGGCUGUUAGAGGGGUGAGUGACAAGUCUUACAAGUGGCCUUAUUCCAACUCCAGAAAUUGCCCAACGGAACUUUGAGAUUAUAUGCAAUCGAAAGUGACAGGAAACAUGCCAACUCAAUCCCUCUUAAUGUACAUGGAUGGGCCAGAAGUGAUUGGCAGCUCUCUUGGCAGUCCGAUGGAGAUGGAGGAUGCCUUGUCAAUGAAAGGGACCGCUGUUGUUCCAUUCCGAGCUACACAAGAAAAAAAUGUCAUCCAAAUCGAGGGGUAUAUGCCCUUGGAUUGCAUGUUCUGCAGCCAGACCUUCACACAUUCAGAAGACCUUAAUAAACAUGUCUUAAUGCAACACCGGCCUACCCUCUGUGAACCAGCAGUUCUUCGGGUUGAAGCAGAGUAUCUCAGUCCGCUUGAUAAAAGUCAAGUGCGAACAGAACCUCCCAAGGAAAAGAAUUGCAAGGAAAAUGAAUUUAGCUGUGAGGUAUGUGGGCAGACAUUUAGAGUCGCUUUUGAUGUUGAGAUCCACAUGAGAACACACAAAGAUUCUUUCACUUACGGGUGUAACAUGUGCGGAAGAAGAUUCAAGGAGCCUUGGUUUCUUAAAAAUCACAUGCGGACACAUAAUGGCAAAUCGGGGGCCAGAAGCAAACUGCAGCAAGGCUUGGAGAGUAGUCCAGCAACGAUCAACGAGGUCGUCCAGGUGCACGCGGCCGAGAGCAUCUCCUCUCCUUACAAAAUCUGCAUGGUUUGUGGCUUCCUAUUUCCAAAUAAAGAAAGUCUAAUUGAGCACCGCAAGGUGCACACCAAAAAAACUGCUUUCGGUACCAGCAGCGCGCAGACAGACUCUCCACAAGGAGGAAUGCCGUCCUCGAGGGAGGACUUCCUGCAGUUGUUCAACUUGAGACCAAAAUCUCACCCUGAAACGGGGAAGAAGCCUGUCAGAUGCAUCCCUCAGCUCGAUCCGUUCACCACCUUCCAGGCUUGGCAGCUGGCUACCAAAGGAAAAGUUGCCAUUUGCCAAGAAGUGAAGGAAUCGGGGCAAGAAGGGAGCACCGACAACGACGAUUCGAGUUCCGAGAAGGAGCUUGGAGAAACAAAUAAGGGCAGUUGUGCAGGCCUCUCGCAAGAGAAAGAGAAGUGCAAACACUCCCACGGCGAAGCGCCCUCCGUGGACGCGGAUCCCAAGUUACCCAGUAGCAAGGAGAAGCCCACUCACUGCUCCGAGUGCGGCAAAGCUUUCAGAACCUACCACCAGCUGGUCUUGCACUCCAGGGUCCACAAGAAGGACCGGAGGGCCGGCGCGGAGUCGCCCACCAUGUCUGUGGACGGGAGGCAGCCGGGGACGUGUUCUCCUGACCUCGCCGCCCCUCUGGAUGAAAAUGGAGCCGUGGAUCGAGGGGAAGGUGGUUCUGAAGACGGAUCUGAGGAUGGGCUUCCCGAAGGAAUCCAUCUGGAUAAAAAUGAUGAUGGAGGAAAAAUAAAACAUCUUACAUCUUCAAGAGAGUGUAGUUAUUGUGGAAAGUUUUUCCGUUCAAAUUAUUACCUCAAUAUUCAUCUCAGAACGCAUACAGGUGAAAAACCAUACAAAUGUGAAUUUUGUGAAUAUGCUGCAGCCCAGAAGACAUCUCUGAGGUAUCACUUGGAGAGACAUCACAAGGAAAAACAAACCGAUGUUGCUGCUGAAGUCAAGAACGAUGGUAAAAAUCAGGACACUGAAGAUGCACUAUUAACCGCUGACAGUGCGCAAACCAAAAAUUUGAAAAGAUUUUUUGAUGGUGCCAAAGAUGUUACAGGCAGUCCACCUGCAAAGCAGCUUAAGGAGAUGCCUUCUGUUUUUCAGAAUGUUCUGGGCAGCGCUGUCCUCUCACCAGCACACAAAGAUACUCAGGAUUUCCAUAAAAAUGCAGCUGAUGACAGUGCUGAUAAAGUGAAUAAAAACCCUACCCCUGCUUACCUGGACCUGUUAAAAAAGAGAUCAGCAGUUGAAACUCAGGCAAAUAACCUCAUCUGUAGAACCAAGGCGGAUGUUACUCCUCCUCCGGAUGGCAGUACCACCCAUAACCUUGAAGUUAGCCCCAAAGAGAAGCAAACGGAGACCGCAGCUGACUGCAGAUACAGGCCAAGUGUGGAUUGUCACGAAAAACCUUUAAAUUUAUCCGUGGGGGCUCUUCACAAUUGCCCGGCAAUUUCUUUGAGUAAAAGUUUGAUUCCAAGUAUCACCUGUCCAUUUUGUACCUUCAAGACAUUUUAUCCAGAAGUUUUAAUGAUGCACCAGAGACUGGAGCAUAAAUACAAUCCUGACGUUCAUAAAAACUGUCGAAACAAGUCCUUGCUUAGAAGUCGACGUACCGGAUGCCCGCCAGCGUUGCUGGGAAAAGAUGUGCCUCCCCUCUCUAGUUUCUGUAAACCCAAGCCCAAGUCUGCUUUCCCGGCGCAGUCCAAAUCCCUGCCAUCUGCGAAGGGGAAGCAGAGCCCUCCUGGGCCAGGCAAGGCCCCUCUGACUUCAGGGAUAGACUCUAGCACUUUAGCCCCAAGUAACCUGAAGUCCCACAGACCACAGCAGAAUGUGGGGGUCCAAGGGGCCGCCACCAGGCAACAGCAAUCUGAGAUGUUUCCUAAAACCAGUGUUUCCCCUGCACCGGAUAAGACAAAAAGACCCGAGACAAAAUUGAAACCUCUUCCAGUAGCUCCUUCUCAGCCCACCCUCGGCAGCAGUAACAUCAAUGGUUCCAUCGACUACCCCGCCAAGAACGACAGCCCGUGGGCACCUCCGGGAAGAGACUAUUUCUGUAAUCGGAGUGCCAGCAAUACUGCAGCAGAAUUUGGUGAGCCCCUUCCAAAAAGACUGAAGUCCAGCGUGGUUGCCCUUGACGUUGACCAGCCCGGGGCCAAUUACAGAAGAGGCUAUGACCUUCCCAAGUACCAUAUGGUCAGAGGCAUCACAUCACUGUUACCGCAGGACUGUGUGUAUCCGUCGCAGGCGCUGCCUCCCAAACCAAGGUUCCUGAGCUCCAGCGAGGUCGAUUCUCCAAAUGUGCUGACUGUUCAGAAGCCCUAUGGUGGCUCCGGGCCACUUUACACUUGUGUGCCUGCUGGUAGUCCAGCAUCCAGCUCGACGUUAGAAGGUCUUGGUGGAUGUCAGUGCUUACUCCCCAUGAAAUUAAAUUUUACUUCAUCCUUUGAGAAGCGAAUGGUGAAAGCUACUGAAAUAAGCUGUGAUUGUACUGUACAUAAAACAUAUGAGGAAUCUGCAAGGAACACUACAGUUGUGUAAAGUUGUUCUGUUAACUUUUGUACCAAAUAGCAAUACAAACUAGUUGGAACAGUUGGAACUUACAUACAUGGGGACUGGAAAUCUCUAUUUUGUCCCUGAAUAAUAUUUUUCUUAGAAUUGACCAAAUAAGAAGUGGAAUUUUUGCAUACUUGAGCGCUGCUGAAAAGAAAUCAUUUGGGUUGGGUGGGGCGGGAUGGGGGAAAAGUAUAUAAUGCUUGCACCUCAGGUAAAAAUCUGUAAAUAUCUAAGUUGUAAACCUGCUUGUUCAAAUACUGUGUGUAUUCCUUUUCUCUAAUGCAGCUCAUCACUUGGAGCAGUUUCUGCUAUUGUGCUCUUUCAUUUAAAAUGUAUGUUUUUUUUUUUUUAAACUGUCAAUGAUUUUGUAUUAUGUUGAAUCCACCCAAAUCUAUUGUUGUCUUAAAAUUGUUAAUGGAAGUAUUGACCCUCUAUGAUAUGUGCUGCAGAUAUCGAGGUCAGCCAUUCGGAAGCUGGCAGCAUUUUAUCGCAACUUUGAGCAUCUCAGAUGGGGAAGGCACCUUCUUCCUCGCCUCUCCAGAUUGUCCUGGAACCUCCAGGAUCCUUGACUGAGGGCGUUGGGAUGGCUUGUAGGAUUUUUAAGAGAGUGUGUCUACAGACAAGCAUUUUCUCUGUAGAGCAGCCACACGUUGUAUAAACAUAAACUGUAUGUGCAGUUAUUUAAAUUUGUUUCUGUCAAAUUAAUCAUUUUUGUUGGACGAUUCAGUGGCGGGGGGGUUUUGCCUAAAUUAGUAUAUAAAAACAAAAAUGCUAAAUUAUAUCUGUGAAUUGCAGGUAUUGGGGAACAGUUUUAAGGGAAAUUUUGGGGGGAACAUUUUAGGUUUGUAUUUGGUAGUCUUAAUGUAUCUGGCAUUUGGGUGAACUGUGGACAUACUAGAGUUGAUUAUAGACACAUUGAUUUUGAAUAAGGAACUGCUGGCCGAGCCCGCUGGGAGUCUAGAAAGAGAAAAUCUGUUUCUAGACCUCAGUUAUUUUCCCAUUUUUGGUUGUUUUGAAGCAGUAACAUUUUUCUCAGUGCACAUGCAAUUUGGGUUUUAGAGAAGAUGGCCACCAGCUGGCUUCCUAGAUAUUUUAAACUUUUGUUCUUUAAUAUGCUGUCCAUGGCUGAGUUUAUUAGUACAUGGGCUUAGUGACCACAAAAUAUUUUAUUAAGAAACUGUUUCAAAAAUAAAUUUGCACUGUUCAUUUUUCUGGCCUCGCUGUUCUCCAUAGAGCAAGGGUAAUCCUAGAAAAAAUUUUUUUUUUUUAAAUUAUGCAACGUAAGAUGUCCUCCUUGAUAGAAGUCUUAGCUCCUGUGUUACAAGGGAGAACUCAUUUGAGAUCAGUCUGUUGGCAUUGCAAUGAAGUGCUUUGUAUCAGGAAAGUGUACACUAUUGACCUUUUUUCCUGUUCACAAGCUGAGCCAUAUGUACAUAAUCUAGAUUUUGUUUUCAUAGUUUUGCACUUUUAUAGCCUAUUUUUGAAGAUUAACACAUUUGCAAGAUGAUUGACUCAAUCUUUGCCUAAUCCAAUGAGUGUUACAGAGAGCUUGCUGUGACUAGAACCAUAAAUCUUAAAGGGGGUAUGUGAUAAUAGAGGGCUGGAAUUUAAACCUGUAUUUAAAAAAAAGAAUCACCAAAUCUAUUUGAAAACAAGUCGAUUUGUAUUAUGCUGGAAUUUUUUGGGCUUUCAGAUUUCUCUUUUUAACCACAUUUCUGAAUGUAUAAAAAUACCAAUUAUUUUCCUACAGCCCUUUGUACUUCAAAAUAUGUUUUUGUGUCCAUCAGUAUUAACUAUUGGUAUACUACUGGUUUUAUAUUUUUUUUUCUUUGAGACAACAGUACAUAUAAUAGAGGUACAAUUCGUUGGAUUUUUGUUUAUGUAUUUAUUUCAUUCCAGUUUGAUUUAUUUUAAUUGUUGAUACUUAAGUUGUCGAACAGUAGACAUUACUUGUUUUAUUUAUGAUAUAUUUCAGCUUAAAGUUAUGUUAUUAUAUGUGGAAGUGUAAAUAUAGAUUUGGUGUUUUGCAA